GCUCCCCUCUCCGACCCUUUGAGCCGUGGCCGUUGCCAGAUGUCCACAAUGGGAAACGAGGCCAGUUACCCGGCGGAGAUGUGCUCCCACUUUGACAAUGAUGAAAUUAAAAGGCUGGGCAGGAGGUUUAAGAAGUUGGACUUGGACAAAUCAGGGUCUCUGAGCGUGGAGGAGUUCAUGUCCCUGCCGGAGCUGCGCCACAACCCGUUGGUGCGGCGAGUGAUCGACGUCUUCGACACCGACGGUGAUGGAGAAGUGGACUUCAAGGAAUUCAUCCUGGGGACCUCCCAGUUCAGCGUCAAGGGCGACGAGGAGCAGAAGUUGAGGUUUGCGUUCAGCAUUUACGACAUGGAUAAAGAUGGCUACAUUUCCAACGGGGAGCUCUUCCAGGUGCUGAAGAUGAUGGUGGGCAACAACCUGACGGACUGGCAGCUCCAGCAGCUGGUCGACAAAACCAUCAUCAUCCUGGACAAGGAUGGCGAUGGGAAGAUAUCCUUUGAGGAAUUCAGUGCUGUGGUCAGAGACCUGGAGAUCCACAAGAAGCUGGUCCUCAUCGUAUGAGCCUUUUUCUUACAAGCACCACCCAACAACUUCUGCUUUCUUCCCUAUCUCUUUCAAGAUUUGCUCAAGACGUCCAACUGUCUCUCUGACUUAUCUGGAAGUAUUUCUUUUUGUGAAGCCAUAUGUCCUAACAGGAGCUUCAUCACCAACUCAGUGCUAUUAAUUCUCCUUCUCUGAAUGACUCAGGGUACCCUAUAGGGGGAAGAGCAAGUCAAAUGAGCAUAGUGGGGAAAGAAAAGGAAAUGGCUUUUAUAAACAUCUUUUACUUUGUUUUGAUUCAAAGACCAAACUAGAACUUUAAAAGUUCAAAAAUAAGAAAGUAUACAUUUUUGCUGUUAUUUCUCAUCAUUUUGUAUAUGGGAGGAAAUUUAUAAUUUGCAUGGGUGUUAGGUGAACUGUUUUCAUUUGCUUGUGUUCAGAUAUCUUGCCAGAUUGUUAACUUCCUAUUGUAGCAACAGGGACAAAUAUAUUUGUCUUUGCUGGGCAUCUCGUAAUCACUUUUCUUAGGGGACAGAAUCCCAUCUUUUCCUUCGGCAGAUUGCAGCCCCAUUCCCCACAAUGCAUCCAGAAAUCGCUGUGCAUGUUUGAGGGGUAGGAGUUCAUUUGGCCUCCUCCUGACUUGUUGCUCCAGCUCCUGAACAGAAACUAGCUUCAGGGCUCUUAUAGGAAAUGCUAAGCCUGGACUAAGUGCCCAGCUCAGCCAUCAUCCUCAUUAGCAGUGGGUUUCCAGGGUUGGCAGCCCACACCAGCAUUAAUUUCAAUGAAGGGGACCUCCAGCUAAAUAGGGCAAGCAAAGUGUUCUCCCAGAAAGUGCUCUCACCUCCGACACUGGUCCCUACCCCCAGGUGGAGACAAUGAGACAUUUAGUUAGUUGUCCUACGGAGGAGAGGCAGUAGAGUCAGGCUGCAGUGGAAUCUCCCUAGGAUGCCAAAGUGGCAUUAUGUCUGUUGCUCACAGAUGCAGAGACUGACAAUUGUGUCUCCACAGCAGAGGUGGAUGCUAGCUACACCAGCUAUGCUGAUUUUGAAAAUCAGAUCUGAGGCCUAGAAGAGAAACUGAGAGCUCUCUCAUUCCAGGAAGCCUUUUCCCUAGUGGAACAUUCAGUGCAGAAGUCCUCACACACUAACAGAUCUCCACCAUUGGGUGAGCCGGAGCCUGUGGUUCCAGGGGAGAUCCAGAAUGCAUGUGUCUCUUCCCACGCAUUUAUGUCAUGUUGGUAGCUUUAGAUCAGCCAUGGUGAGAAAAGAACAAAAGCUUUUAGUUGUUUUUGUUUUGUUUUGGAGAAUUUGUUUACCAGUAAAUACAUCACUGCCUGUACCCCAAAUGUUACCAGCUCCCUGAGGUGUCCCACAUACUAUUGUGAGUUCUCAGAGCAUGAACUGUCCUCAGAAGAGCAGGGCUAGGACUUGUCCCAGCAUCUGUGCCUCCAUACCAAUCCUCUUUCUCACAGAGAACCACUUCCCAUAUAAGAUGCUUAAGGCUCUCAAAACAGCAGAACAAUGAAACAUACUCUCCCUACACUUGCUUAGCCAAGAGAUACCACUCAGGUAACUUUUUUCAGGACAUGGAAGAUCUGUUUCAAGGAGAUUUACUGCUAUUUUAUUUGGAAGAAGCUGGCAACUGGUCUUGACCAAAAUAGAAAAAAAAAAAAAAAGUCCACAAAUUUAAUCACUUGUAGGGAACCCAUCUAUCAAGGUACCCUACCAUAUACUUUUGUAUUUAAUAGAUUACUUAGAAACCACAAAAAUAGGAAUCCUUACCCCUUCAAUUCCUGUUCAACCCUAAAAACUGUGAUAAACGCUCCCAACCCUGUGGUGAUCAGGGUUAUGUAAUGUUCAAAGAUUCAGACACACCUGGGUUUGGAUUCAGUUGCAACUGGGUUGUUAUCACACUCACUUCUUUUUAGCUGUGUGAGCAUGAAUAAUUUACUUAGCCUCUCUGUGUCUUUCCACCUAAUUAAAGAGGAUCCACCCCAGGGUUAUUUUGAGGAUUCAAAAAGGCAUGCAACACACCUGGAGCACAAUUCCACUUUCAUUCAACUAAUUCCCUUCCCUUCCCCCUUCUUCCCCUUCUACAAGAUCAAUAUGUAAAGGAGACAUGAGGCUUACUGGUUGCUUUUGAACACUUACUUAGUUCUUAGCUACACCCACUCUAAAAUUAACUGGACAUUAGUGUACAGCCCAUGUCCAAGCCCAGAGAGAAAACAAUGGGAACAAUUUCAAGGUCCUCACCACUCCUUCAUUUGCAGAGGGGACAACAGACUUUCUGACCUGAGAACUGGAGAAUUUUUAAAACAAAAUCUCUCAUUCCAGCCCAACCUAUUUAACUUUUUGUGGAGGAAUUUUACAUGGAGGAAGUGAGCACAUGUCAUGCUAGCCAAGAGGACAUUAUUGUCAUUAAAGAGAGGCAUUAUUUAUACACCCUGCAAUGUGCACAUUAAAAUAUGGAAAUUUUAAAAUUAUGACCAAGGGCUUGAAACAUAUUGGAUUACAUGCUCACAUUUAACAAAGAGAGGAAAUGUGUUUCAGUUUCUGGAGUGGCUGGAAUUUACAAGCUAAUUGUUCAAUAAAUCUACUCAAGAUAGUUACCUAAGGCUUUGUGGCAAUGACCUUGAACUGAGAGCCUGUAUCUGGAUUUAGCACUUGAAAGAUCUAACUGGAUAUUUGGGUUAAAAGAAUCACAUUUAUUCCCAAAUCGGAAUGCUUUGUUUUUCCUGUCAGUUAAUUGCCAGUUGCCAACAAAUCUAGUUCUAUACAGUUUCUUGGGAUGAUGAUAAUAAACAUUUAUUGAGCAAUUGUCCCAUAA